CUAAACUCACUUGACGAGGUUCUUUGAUAAAACUGCAUUUUACAAGGAAGUGCACAAAUGGGCCUAGAAGGUUCAGGGGCCUGAGUAAAAUUUCGUCAAGAAAAGAAUCUUUCUCAUUGUUGGAAAGUACACUUCCCAAUUUCCAAAACUUUAUAGAAAAUACAAGUAAAGGUUUCCAAAUGGAAAUAAUAGAUAAGCAACUGAUAAAAAGCAUGUGAAGCAUAGCCUAACUCUGCUUCAACCUAUACAUUACAAAAUGAUGGAUAUAUGAAUUAACCCUUUUAUGCCACUGCCUUUAUUUAGAAGAAUGAGGCUGGUAAUUUCGGGUUUAUAACCCAAAAUGUGUUUUUACUUUGUUUUAACUAAUGAAAUUAUUAUCAAACGUAUUGAAAAUAUAAACUAUCCAACCUAAUAUUGAUUGUUACCAACUUACCCAAUGGAUAUACAAAUAUCCUGCAGCUACAGAUGUUUUCUCUGCCCGCUGGGGUUUUUAGUGGCGCUUAUUGGGAAGGACUGAAAGUAGAGGGCAGUGACAAUUGGGAAUCGCUAUGGAGAUAUCCCUGAGAAGUGAUGGUCACAGCUGACCUGUCUCCUUUAUGGUAGAUGAGGGUAGGGACACUUUUUCUUCUCUCUGAACGUACUGCAGUUAGAUUUAUUUAGCUUAAAAAUAACAAAUACAGAAAUAUUUAGAUGGAAAUGACUAGAACUGUCAGUUAUUCUAUUUUAAUGUGAAUGGAUUUAAUCAGAUUGCUUUCUUCUUGGUUAGCUACACUAAGGAAGUGGGAGUUUUGACUUGAGGAGGGAUAGUAGAUGUAAGUAUUAUGAGAUCGUGGAACAUUUUGGAAUAUUGGGCAAAGUUUGCCCUACUUCUAAAAGUGAGGAUGUUAAAAAAUGGAAAGCUUUAGAUAGCAUGAGGGAUCUGAAAGAUGAGAAAAGAAAAGCAAGAAUGAAACAAUUUGGAAGGAAAGAUUGUAGGAUAUAAAGACAGAUUCGACUUAUUUAGACAUUUUUGCCCAAGAAAAAUGUCUAAAUAGGAAAAGUGGAAACCUUUUCCUUCAUUUGAUCCCUCUUUCCUUUUGCCCCACCUUGCUGCUCCAUGCUAACUGUUCUCCUAGGACCCAGAAAUCAGACUGGGAUUACUGUUGUUCAUGUUGAAGCUUUCAAGUGUGCUAGUUACACCCCUUCUCUCUCCAUAUUCUAGUCAAAUUGAGAUCAGACUCAAGCCAGAUAAGAAUUUAAAUACUAUUAAAAUAAUAGUGUAAUUUUCAUUUCCGGUAAAGCUGGAUUGGAGAACUGAGCUUAGACCCAUGCUUACUGUUCUUUCUUAAUUUACCUACCCAGAUGAAACUGUUGCACCAGGAAAUGGAAGGGAAAGUCCUGUCCUAAGGAGCUUAUCUUAUAGCAGUUAGAAUGGAAAGGAAAACUUUCUCUCCUUGAGGGCACAGCAAGUCCAAGAAAGCCAGUGAGAGCUCACGGGUGGAGCCUGUCUGAACAGUUGACCUUUAUACCUAUCCUAGCAAUUAGAUAAGUCACUUUCCUGUGGGAGGAAUUAGUGAUGGGGGUGGAGAGAAAGAAAAGUGUUCCUUUAAUCUUGUUUUCUCCUACUUAGAGGAGUGAAAGUUCUGUUGUCAUUGCAGAGAGAAGUAAACAGCCAUCCUCUCAUAGUUAAGUAUGUUAUGGGAAAUAAAUAGUGUUUUGUAGGCUAGCCUAGGAACUAAUUCACCAUUUAUAAAAAUGAACUGACUGUAUAUUUUCCUUGGAAAUAACUAAAUCUCUUAGACACUUUUGAGUGAUUAUUUUAUUGUGUAGUUAAAUAUAUAGAUUAUUCAAGUCUAUUUCCUUGUUUUACCAGUACUGGUUAAAUAUUUAUGGAAUGUCUAAUACGUGACAGGCACUGGGCUAGGCUUUGGGAUUCAGUGGUGAACAAGAAUGGGUCCUUGCUCUAAGAGUUACAACCUAGAAAAACAGUUAGUACAAGUACCAUUACGAUAAAGCGUAAUAAGCAUUGGUUAAGUGUAGAGUGCUUUGGAACCACAGAAGAAGGAGAACUUAUCUAUGAGGGCCAGGGACAUGGAUGUUAAAGAGCUGAGAUCUUAAGCUGAAUAGGAAGUAGCUAGGUAAAAGGGAAGAGUGAGGUUGAGCAGAAGUGUUUUGAGCAAAAAGAACAUGUGGAAAGGCCAAGAGGUGUGAGAAUGUGGUACACUAAAGUGACAUUUUUUUUCUUUAACUGCAGGCACCUACUAGUAGAUUGUGAAAGCAAAUUAGUGAGUUGUAAUCCACAUGUUUUUUAAAAGGAAUACAAUAGAAAAUGAGGGUGUGCCACUCAUAGAUACUUACUGGAUUGUAGGGGUAAGUAGGGGUGUUUAUGCAGGAUUUAGUUAACCUUAUUAAAGAAGUUGGAUUUAUCUUAGAGGAAAUGACAAAUCAUUGAAAAGUUCUAAUCGGGGCCUGAUUAGAGAUCUUUAGAAAAAGGUCUCUUUGGGUACCUGGUCUUUCUUAACUCGGAUGUAAACUUCAAAUUCAUUGGCCCAGCAUUACAGGUAUUCCAAAACCUGGUUCCAAUCUAUUUCUUGUAAAAAAUCUUCCCACUAUUUUUGUUAUUGGAAUUUCCCAGUUCAUAAAGAUUCGUUCGCCUAAGUACCUUUGCACCAAGACCAAAAGGUCUGUGAGAACAGAUUUCACUUCUGUCCUUUAACAUUGAGUCUCUGGCAACUAGUAUAGUGCCUGGCUCACAAUAGAGACUAAGCAAAUCUUCGUUGAUAGAGUCUAAAUACCUUUAAUAUUAGGAACAUUAUGCAGUAGUAGACAUGACGUUGCUGUUUCUGGUAAUGUCUGCUUUGGGACAAAGAAAAAGUUUUCAUUCAAAUUUUUUUUCUCAGUUGAAAUCAUGUUAAUGAUAGAACUGCAUACAUUUAUUAAAAAGAUAAUUUAACAGAGGGCAUUCUUACAUUGAAACAGUAGUAGAGAUAAUAAAAAGAACAAUAAACAUUGUGGUUUUGAUGUUUUCCCAGGGAGUACAGUGACACAGAUUGCUCACAGGAGCAGCCAAUCCAGAAAUCAUUUCUGUUUUGUUUGAACUUAGAGGCAUUCUCUGAGCACUCACCCAAAGGCAGUGUUAGAAAAAUGGCUAAGGACAAAAGGAAUAAAUUAUUAGGUUGGUGCAAAAGUAAGUGCAGUUUUUGCAAUUAAAAGUAAUGACAAAAACUGCAAUUACUUUUGCACCAACCUAAAUGGAUGAAAAUAUAUCAAUCAUAUGAGCUUAAUGAAGAAUCAACAGAAAAUAGAUUUUGUUCUUACAAAUGAAAAUAGAACAUCCAUAUACCCUAAAGAAUUUACAAAUAAGAAUUUAAUGAUGUCAGUUUGUUGCCAGAGCAUGAUUCUACUGUCACAGUAUUAUGACUUCACAGAAUUAAAUUGUGAAACCCAACCAUAAAGGAAAAAUUCUUUCAGUGUUUGGUUCCGAUCAGUGGUAAAAGAAGUUACGAACAGUUCAUAAAAGAUCCAGUCCUUCUGUGGAACUUCUGAACAUCUUUUAUUAGUGGAAAUAUUUUCUACACAAUGAAGUCAACAACUUAAUUUAAACCAGUGUUUGUGCGGUUCUGAUUCAUCUGCUGUGGUUCCCGAAGCUUGAGAUCUAAGGAGUACAGGGUCUUUUGUGAUGACAAUAUGACUAAUAGUAAAGGAAGAUCUAUUACCGAUAAAACAAGUGGUGGUCCAAGUAGUGGAGGAGGUUUUGUAGAUUGGACUUUACGUUUAAACACAAUUCAAUCCGACAAGUUUUUAAAUUUACUCUUGAGUAUGGUUCCAGUGAUUUACCAGAAAAACCAAGAAGACAGGCACAAAAAAGCAAACGGCAUUUGGCAAGAUGGAUUAUCAACUGCAGUACAGACUUUUAGUAAUAGAUCUGAGCAACACAUGGAGUAUCACAGUUUCUCAGAGCAGUCUUUUCAUGCCAAUAAUGGGCACGCAUCAUCAAGCUGCAGCCAAAAGUAUGAUGACUAUGCCAAUUAUAAUUACUGUGAUGGAAGGGAGACUUCAGAAACCACUGCCAUGUUACAAGAUGAAGAUAUAUCUAGUGAUGGUGAUGAAGAUGCUAUUGUAGAAGUGACCCCAAAAUUACCAAAGGAAUCCAGUGGCAUCAUGGCAUUGCAAAUACUUGUGCCCUUUUUGCUAGCUGGUUUUGGAACAGUUUCAGCUGGCAUGGUACUGGAUAUAGUACAGCACUGGGAGGUGUUCAGAAAAGUUACAGAAGUUUUCAUUUUAGUCCCUGCACUUCUUGGUCUCAAAGGGAACUUGGAAAUGACAUUGGCAUCCAGAUUAUCCACUGCAGUAAAUAUUGGGAAGAUGGAUUCACCCAUUGAAAAGUGGAACCUAAUAAUUGGCAACUUGGCUUUAAAGCAGGUUCAGGCAACAGUAGUGGGUUUUCUAGCAGCUGUGGCAGCAAUUAUAUUGGGCUGGAUUCCAGAAGGAAAAUAUUACCUUGAUCAUUCCAUACUUCUGUGCUCUAGCAGUGUGGCAACUGCCUUCAUUGCAUCUCUUCUGCAGGGAAUAAUAAUGGUUGGGGUUAUCGUUGGUUCAAAGAAGACUGGUAUAAAUCCUGAUAAUGUUGCUACACCCAUUGCUGCUAGUUUUGGCGACCUUAUAACUCUUGCCAUAUUGGCUUGGAUAAGUCAGGGCUUAUACUCCUGUCUUGAGACCUAUUACUACAUUUCUCCAUUAGUUGGUGUAUUUUUCUUGGCUCUAACCCCUAUUUGGAUUAUAAUAGCUGCCAAACAUCCAGCCACAAGAACAGUUCUCCACUCAGGCUGGGAGCCUGUCAUAACAGCUAUGGUUAUAAGUAGCAUUGGGGGCCUUAUUCUGGACACAACUGUAUCAGACCCAAACUUGGUUGGGAUUGUUGUUUACACGCCAGUUAUUAAUGGUAUUGGUGGUAAUUUGGUGGCCAUUCAGGCUAGCAGGAUUUCUACCUACCUCCAUUUACAUAGCAUUCCAGGAGAAUUGCCUGAUGAACCCAAAGGUUGUUACUACCCAUUUAGAACUUUCUUUGGUCCAGGAGUAAAUAAUAAGUCUGCUCAAGUUCUACUGCUUUUAGUGAUUCCUGGACAUUUAAUUUUCCUCUACACUAUUCAUUUGAUGAAAAGUGGUCAUACUUCUUUAACUAUAAUCUUCAUAGUAGUGUAUUUAUUUGGCGCUGUGUUACAGGUAUUUACCUUGCUGUGGAUUGCUGACUGGAUGGUCCAUCACUUCUGGAGGAAAGGAAAGGACCCGGAUAGUUUCUCCAUCCCCUACCUAACAGCAUUGGGUGAUCUGCUCGGGACAGCUCUGUUAGCCUUAAGUUUUCAUUUUCUUUGGCUUAUUGGAGAUCGAGAUGGAGAUGUUGGAGACUAAUAAAUUCUACAAACUGCUCUCAAGUUACCAAGGAAGAAAAUACACGACAACCACUUAUGGCUCUUUUUCAAAACUCUUAAAUCAGUAGUUUGACUUUUGCCAGGGUAAUCUUCAGUUGGCCCUGAUUCAAUUAAAUGGCCUUAAUUUUUUUUUAAGGAAUUUGUGUCAAAACCAGAAUGAAGAGUAUUCGUGCUGCUUUUCAUAGAAUAAAUGAUAAUUUGACAUAGACAUAGAUAUAAGUUCCAGCUCUGAAAUUAAUUAGGAAAGAAUAUAGGAUGUUUACAGUGAAUAAUUUUAAAACCACAAACAUAGCAGAAAUGUACUUUAUUAUUAAAUUUGUAAUGCAGGAUUAGAAGAAGCAGAGCUCUAGUUUAGCCUUUCUUGUCUCACAGAUGUGCUGUAUCCCAGGCAUACUAUAAAACGAAGAGUGCCCAACCAAGCUUUGAAUCGUAUUAACAAUGCCCACCUCUAUGCUAGCUGAGGAUAAAUUUACCAGUUGCUCAUAUUUAAACUGACCUAAAUAUGUUUUGCUGAGCAUAAGAUAAACUCACUUUUACCUCCAUCUAAAAUUAUCCUGUUCUGAUGCCAAUUCAAUUUCAGCUCUGCAAGUUCUUGUCAGGCUAAUCUUUAAACAUUGAGUGAUCUUGAGAGAUUGUUAAUGAAAGCAGUGAGUCAUUUUUUGAUGAUUGAUUUGUUGGAAAAAUGUUGAUGUGUUUUAAAAAAUGUAAUCUUCAAAAACAGAAUAUAACCUGAGAUGCAUUUGUAGAGACAAGACGGUACGAGAAUGUGUGUGUGUGUGUGUGUGAGAGAGAGAGACUUUUGAUGAAGAACUAAAUCUUGGAUUGCUGAUAGCAAAGAUCAUAGUGCUGUUGGAAUAUCAGCAAUAUAGAGUUAUUCUUAAACACAUUCUAUUAACAUGUUUUUGUCAUUGGGUCCAAAAAUUUUGCUGCUGACCAGAAUUUACUAUUUGUUACCUAUAUUCUUUUUUUUUUUUUUUUUUUUUUUUUUUGAGACAGAGUCUUGCUCUGUCGCCCAGGCUGGAAUGCAGUGGUGUGAUCUCGGCUCACUGCUACCUCCACCUCCUGGAUUCAAGUGAUUCUCCUGCCUCAGCCUCCCGAGUAGCUGGGAUUACAGGAAUGCGCCACAACGCCCAGCUAAUUUGUUACCUACACUCUAAUUAAUAAUUAAUAAUUUCUUAUUUUAAAAAGUAGUACUAUUUAAUAUAAUCAAGAUAGGAGAUUUAAAAUGAGCAAGUGAUUCAUUUGCUCUUUUAAAGAAGCCCGUUGACUUACGCUUUUAAAAAAGAAGUUGGUGGGUUACCUCAAUUAUUGUUCAUGCUUAAACAUAUCCAUUUGUACAGGCUUAUUUCUACGUGGGACCCAAUCAUAUAUACUAUAUUUCUCAAAUAAUUUUUCUAAAACUCUGGCCUAUAUUCUAAACACUUGACCAACACCUUAGUUAUUGAAUAGGUAACCAUUUUUAAAGUACAUGUGGUUCAUUUUUUAAAAUUCAAUCUCUCAAGACCGUUAGAUAUUUAAUAAUUUAAGCUGAUAAGGGUAUCAAAAUGCACAUUAACUUUGAUCAUCAUGAUUUAAGUUGUAACUUUGUGUUAUUAUAUAAAUAUUAGGUUGUUUAUAAAUAUAUUGCAGAAAGUAUUCUUGUUAAGCUCUUUUAAAUGAGGGGACUGUGGUUUAGAGUUAUAUAUUUUUGCUUAUUUUUAAACUUCAAUUAUUCCAUUCUUCUGCCUUAUAAUAAAACUUUUAAGGCAGAGAACUGAACUAAUUAUAGAAUUUCUCCUUUGGAGAGUUAUAAUGUUACAUAGUGAACAUUCUUAUAAAAGAAAGAAUAAGUUUAAGUUGAUGAAUAUUUAGCUGCAAAGAUUUUUUACUUAAAAAAAUCCAUGAAUAUCUUUGAUUUUAUUAUAAAGCAUUUGUAAAUUAUUUGCAUUUGAGCUGUAAGAUUCAUAAACAUUUACAUUUCCCAAUGAUUUCUAUUUUGAUUUUUAAAAAAUAUACAGGGCAAGCUACAUUUUUAAAGCAUUAAUCAACAACUUUAUUAUAUUACACAUUCCAGUGCACAAACACACAAUAUCAUUUAAUACUCACAGUAGUACCUGUGAAAUAUAUCAGAUGGAUAUUCCUAUCUCUAUUUUACAGCAGAGGAAACCGAAAUUCAGAGAACUUACAUUUCUAAGGUUGUACAGCUGCAAAAUGACCAAAUUGUGAAGUCCCUAACAUCCAGGUUUUCAUAAUGCCAGUACUCUUUCUAUGACAUGUUUAUGACCCUCCAAAUGUACCAAAACUACCUAACUAAUUCACUGAGAGGAAGCCAACUGCAAAAAUAGGAUUUUUAAAAGUACAAUAGAGUAUUACUACAUUUUAUGGAUUUCAGACAAAGAAACCUCCGUUUAUUAUAUCCUGAUGGUGAGUAUUGCCAGCUCUAAAUUAUUCAUAUUUCUAAGACCAAGGAAAAUAUAGGUAAAUGAAAAUUUUGAAAUAAAGAACAAUGCCUUAAUUUGUAAAAUCUAUCAUUGCUACCACCCUGCCCAGGUCUGGCCAUUUGCCAUAAAUGCUGGUAAAUAAAUACAAUGACUGAUAGAGUUCUGUCUCCUUUCUCUUUUGCUACCCAACCUUGGUUAGAGCAACCAAAUGUCUAAAAGGCAUGUAACAGGAGAAAAAAAUAAAAACAUUAGUCACCAAUUCGCCGAUUAUAAAAGGGAUGUAGAUUCCUUUAAAUUAUUACUGACCUUUUGAAAGCCUUCACGUAAGUAUGCAACAGAUAAAAUGACUCAUUUACCCACAACAAUAAUCUAUUAUCAGUCUUAAGUAAUGUGAAUUCACUGUAUUUCUUUUUAUACAACAUAAAAACUUCUGCUUUCCAAACUUCUUCCUUUUCACUAAUUUAUCAGCCACUUUAUUUAUACACAGAUAACACUUUUAGAAACAUUUUUCUUUCUUGUCCAUUUUUUUCUUUCAAAAAUAAAGUUUCUUAGAACCUGAUAAAAUGGAAACUUAUGGUAAUAUGUGUUCUGGUAGGUGUCCAAAAAUUCCACACCAUAGACUAUCAAUGAUAUAGCCAAAUAAAGGCCAUUCAAAAAAAUCAGUAAUUGGGAUUCCUUGCCUUAUAUCUAUGGUAUAGUGUACCCAUUUAUAACGGGGUUCUGCCAUCUUCGAAUUGUUUUAAACUCAAAUAAAGAAUAAAAUUUAAGAAAUAAUUAUCCAGUCUUGUUAUGCUUACUUCUUGAUGAACUAGAGAACAUCAAGCCAGUGUGGAAAUCUCCCAGAAGAGACUGGGGUAAUUUAUGUAUACAUAUGAUAUUUAUGAAUUAUAAUAAAUUGGGCUUUGACCAUA